GUAAACGUCUGACCUGGGGCCGUCGCUUAACCGUUUAGUUGCUGGGAUGGGGCGGCGUUGGGGGUGCGGCCCUGAACCGGAGGGAUUUAGAGACUGGAGACGCGGCCUCUAAGAGAGGUUGAAACUGUGUGUGUGUGGGAGAAAAUGAUAACCACCCUCCCAUCUCUCCUACCCGCCAGCCUCGCCAGUAUCUCCCACCGAGUCACGAAUCUCCCAUCUAACUCCCUCUCACACAACCCAGGCCUCUCCAAGCCUGACUUUCCCGGAAACUCCAGUCCAGGUCUUCCUUCCUCCUCCAGCCCAGGCCGGGACCUGGGGGCUCCUGCCGGAUCCAUGGGGGCGGCCAGCUGCGAGGAUGAGGAGCUGGAAUUUAAGCUGGUGUUCGGGGAGGAAAAGGAGGCCCCCCCGCUGGGCGCGGGGGGAUUGGGGGAAGAACUGGACUCAGAGGAUGCCCCGCCAUGCUGCCGUCUGGCCUUGGGAGAGCCCCCUCCCUAUGGCGCUGCACCUAUCGGUAUUCCCCGACCUCCACCCCCUCGGCCUGGCAUGCAUUCGCCACCGCCGCGACCAGCCCCCUCACCUGGCACCUGGGAGAGCCAGCCCGCCAGGUCGGUGAGGCUGGGAGGACCAGGAGGGGGUGCUGGGGGUGCUGGGGGUGGCCGUGUUCUCGAGUGUCCCAGCAUCCGCAUCACCUCCAUCUCUCCCACGCCGGAGCCGCCAGCAGCGCUGGAGGACAACCCUGAUGCCUGGGGGGACGGCUCUCCUAGAGAUUACCCCCCACCAGAAGGCUUUGGGGGCUACAGAGAAGCAGGGGGCCAGGGUGGGGGGGCCUUCUUCAGCCCAAGCCCUGGCAGCAGCAGCCUGUCCUCGUGGAGCUUCUUCUCCGAUGCCUCUGACGAGGCAGCCCUGUAUGCAGCCUGCGACGAGGUGGAGUCUGAGCUAAAUGAGGCGGCCUCCCGCUUUGGCCUGGGCUCCCCGCUGCCCUCGCCCCGGGCCUCCCCUCGGCCAUGGACCCCCGAAGAUCCCUGGAGCCUGUAUGGUCCAAGCCCCGGAGGCCGAGGGCCAGAGGAUAGCUGGCUACUCCUCAGUGCUCCUGGGCCCACCCCAGCCUCCCCGCGGCCUGCCUCUCCAUGUGGCAAGCGGCGCUAUUCCAGCUCGGGAACCCCAUCUUCAGCCUCCCCAGCUCUGUCCCGCCGUGGCAGCCUGGGGGAAGAGGGGUCUGAGCCACCUCCACCACCCCCAUUGCCUCUGGCCCGGGACCCGGGCUCCCCUGGUCCCUUUGACUAUGUGGGGGCCCCACCAGCUGAGAGCAUCCCUCAGAAGACACGGCGGACUUCCAGCGAGCAGGCAGUGGCUCUGCCUCGGUCUGAGGAGCCUGCCUCAUGCAAUGGGAAGCUGCCCUUGGGAGCAGAGGAGUCUGUGGCUCCUCCAGGAGGUUCCCGGAAGGAGGUGGCUGGCAUGGACUACCUGGCAGUGCCCUCCCCACUCGCUUGGUCCAAGGCCCGGAUUGGGGGACACAGCCCUAUCUUCAGGACCUCUGCCCUACCCCCACUGGACUGGCCUCUGCCCAGCCAAUAUGAGCAGCUGGAGCUGAGGAUCGAGGUACAGCCUAGAGCCCACCACCGGGCCCACUAUGAGACAGAAGGCAGCCGUGGAGCUGUCAAAGCUGCCCCUGGCGGUCACCCCGUAGUCAAGCUCCUAGGCUACAGUGAGAAGCCACUGACCCUACAGAUGUUCAUCGGCACUGCAGAUGAAAGGAACCUGCGGCCUCAUGCCUUCUAUCAGGUGCACCGUAUCACAGGCAAGAUGGUGGCCACGGCCAGCUAUGAAGCCGUAGUCAGUGGCACCAAGGUGUUGGAGAUGACUCUGCUGCCUGAGAACAACAUGGCGGCCAACAUUGACUGCGCGGGAAUCCUGAAGCUUCGGAAUUCAGACAUUGAGCUUCGGAAGGGUGAGACGGACAUCGGGCGCAAAAACACACGUGUACGGCUGGUGUUCCGGGUACACGUGCCCCAGGGCGGCGGGAAGGUCGUCUCAGUACAGGCAGCAUCGGUGCCCAUCGAGUGCUCCCAGCGCUCAGCCCAGGAGCUGCCCCAGGUGGAGGCCUACAGCCCCAGUGCCUGCUCUGUGAGAGGAGGCGAGGAACUGGUACUGACUGGCUCCAACUUCCUGCCAGACUCCAAGGUGGUGUUCAUUGAGAGGGGUCCUGAUGGGAAGCUGCAAUGGGAGGAGGAGGCCACAGUGAACCGACUGCAGAGCAACGAGGUGACGCUGACCCUGACUGUCCCCGAGUACAGCAACAAGAGGGUUUCCCGGCCAGUCCAGGUCUACUUUUAUGUCUCCAAUGGGCGGAGGAAACGCAGUCCUACCCAGAGUUUCAGGUUUCUGCCUGUGAUCUGCAAAGAGGAGCCCCUACCGGACUCAUCUCUGCGGGGUUUCCCUUCAGCAUCGGCAACCCCCUUUGGCACUGACAUGGACUUCUCACCACCCAGGCCCCCCUACCCCUCCUAUCCCCAUGAAGACCCUGCUUGCGAAACUCCUUACCUAUCAGAAGGCUUCGGCUAUGGCAUGCCCCCUCUGUACCCCCAGACGGGGCCCCCACCAUCCUACAGACCGGGCCUGCGGAUGUUCCCUGAGACUAGGGGUACCACAGGUUGUGCCCAACCACCUGCAGUUUCCUUCCUUCCCCGCCCCUUCCCUAGUGACCCGUAUGGAGGGCGGGGCUCCUCUUUCUCCCUGGGGCUGCCAUUCUCUCCGCCAGCCCCCUUUCGGCCGCCUCCUCUUCCUGCAUCCCCACCGCUUGAAGGCCCCUUCCCUUCCCAGAGUGAUGUGCAUCCCCUACCUGCUGAGGGAUACAAUAAGGUAGGGCCAGGCUAUGGCCCUGGGGAGGGGGCUCCGGAGCAGGAGAAAUCCAGGGGUGGCUACAGCAGCGGCUUCCGAGACAGUGUCCCUAUCCAGGGUAUCACGCUGGAGGAAGGUGGGUGUGGGACUGGGGGCUGUGAGUGUGAGUGUGUGCAAGAGAUUGCUCUGCAUGUUUGCUGAGGGCUGGAGCUGGGCUUUUCAGAGAUCGGGCAUCCCUGGUCUCUCAGGGCCAGUUGGAGGUUCCCAGGAGGCAUGUUCUUGAUGCCUGUGGCUGCCUGAAUCCAAUUAACUGAAUUCUGAAGAGUGCAUGGGGUAACUGUCUCAGCCUUUCUCCUGUCUCUGCCUCUGUCCUCUGCUCCAAAUCAUAAAAUCUCAGAGCUAGAAGCACUUUCAAGAUCAUUCCAUCCAGCGCAUUCAAUUUGCAAGUUUAGGCGUUGAGUUCCAGAGAGGGAUGGUAGCUUGCUGAGGUCCCAGUCAAGCACACUUGCCAUUGCCUCAGCUUUCCCCUAAACACGGUGUCUGUGGUCAGGGUUGGUGAGGAGGAGCUUUCCUGUUUUGCCUCUCCUUCUUCCCAUUGGCUACACCCAUCUCUGGCCCUGCUGAUACCGAUUCCCCUGACAUUUCAGGCUAAGCCAGCAGGAAAGGGCUAGGACGGGUGCCUGGGAGCCCACAUGGAGGGAGUUGGGCAAGAUUUGAUUCGGAGCAGGUGUCAAGACGUGUUGGGGAAACUGAGGCCCAGUGGAAUAGAAGCCAGUAGAGGAGGAAUCUAGAGGCCUCCUAGAUUAAGACCUGCCUGGAAUGGAUUGGGGGUGGGUCUUUGGAAAAGGAGGGGACCCACCUCUAGCCCAGUCUCUCAACUGCCCCUCCUUUACAGUGAGUGAGAUCAUUGGCCGAGACCUGAGUGGCUUCCCUGCACCUCCUGGAGAAGAGCCUCCUGCCUGAACCACGUGAACUGUCAUCACCUGGCAACCCCAGCCCCAGCCUCAGCCCUGCCCCCUUUCCCUCCUUCCUGGAGUGGUGGCUACAGAAGCUUGGGGCCAACCCUGGCUCCUCUUUCCCCAGCUUCUGUCUGUCUCACUGUCUUCCCUCCCCUCCCCCAGCUGAGGUGUGGCCCUCAGGCCUGGUGCUGCCUUGGAGGGCUGGGGGAAGGAGUGUGUGGAGGAGGGAGGAGGGUGAAGACUGAGGCUAGGUGCCAGAAUGGACUGGAGUGAAGGCGUGUCUAGAGUGUGGGCUGGCUGUUGUGCUGGAAAGCUGGGGACAGGUUGAUGGUAAUAAACUGCUCAAUGACCAGUGCUUCAGGCUCCAGAGCUCUUUGGAGAGAUGGGUUGGGGCAGCUUACUCCAGCCCUGGCCCAAGGAGGCCCAGAAGUUGGAAAGAGAUGGAAUGUGGCUGGGAACAUUGCAUCCCAAAGAGCUUCUCAGUGGAGGAGGCUGGGGAAGGCAUGAGGGGGCUCAGAGGCUCCUUGACUGGGACCAGGAUUGGGGGCCAGGGCUUGAGUAGGCCUCUCCACUCUCCUCCUUGGGGGUCCAGAUUCCUUAGGAGCUUUGGGAUGAGGCCCAGGAGGCUGCAUUUUUCCAGGUCCUUAGUCUUGCCACCACACAGAUGAUUCUGAUUCAUAGCCAAGAUGAGGACACACUGAUGUAGCUGAUCUCUCAUUUACAGAGGAGGAUUCUAAAGUUCAGAGAGGGAAAGGGGCUUGCCUGAGGUCACGUAGAUAAUCAGCAGCACAUUGAACGCUGCACUCCUGGGCUCCUGUCCCCAGCCCCCAUUCAGACACGCUGACUCAGGAGGUCCAGGCCUCUAAGGCUUCUCUCCCUGGAGUGAGGGUGGAGGUGAGGGAGAGCUGGCACAAGCCCUCCCUCUGGAUCCUCCACUCCUGGGGAUUAUGAAGAUAUUCUGGAAAGAUUUGUGCUUCAGAGGUAGACUGCAGAAAGCAAACAGUCUACCCAGCAGCUCUGAAUGUCACCUGCCCUGGGGCUUACAGCACUAUAUGAGUUCCUGGCCUAUCCUGCAAAUAUGCCCAUGCUGGCCUUCUAAAUAGCUGGUACAUCCAUCACCACUGACGGGCCUGGCCUGGAAACCUGGUUUGUCCCCUGUCUUGAUGGCCUACGAGAGGCCAAGUUCCACUGGGCUGGGAAAAGUCACUUUGUCUGUCUUGUUCACCUGGAGCCUGACACACCGUAGGUACUGAGUACAAAUAGCUUGAUUUGGCUAGGCUUGGCUGCAGGGGGACGUGCCUAAAAGACAUUCCGGGCAUUUGCACUUGGGAAACUUGCCUCACCUUCAGGCUUGUGGGGCCUCUCUAUGCCCAAUGAGUCCAGGCAGUCCUAGCAAGUACUCAGGAGAGCAGGGGUGGGUGUGACAGAGGCUGGCUCUGGAUUGGGGGACAACAGAACCAGAGUAACUCCUCGCCUGUUGCUGCUUUGCAAUGAAUUUCCUUUACCUUUCUGGAACACAAGCUGCUGUGAACCAAACUGAUAUCAAGUGAUUAGCUCACCGGGCCUUGGUUGCUUUUCAAAGAUCCCCUUCAGCCCCCUGCCAGAGUCACUGCCCCAUAAUCACCAUGUCAGAAGGGACCCUAGGGCAUUCGUGUCCUAUUUAUCAAUCUUCAGCACCACCUCUAAGAUCUCUGAGAGAGGGUGGAUCAGCCUCUGUGUAAACAAAAAGCUGUUAGGACUUGUUGCCUCUCAAGGUGGACUAUUCUGUUUUCUGCCAGGACACUGCCAUUCAUGCAUUGUCAGAUAUUUAUUAAACAGCAGCAAAGUGCCAGCCAAUUUGUCCUGGAGGAAUUCAUAGCCUCAUGGGGCAAAAGUAAAUAAACAGCUUAUUACAAUUCAA